AUGCGCGGCGCGGCUGGAGCGGCCGGACAGUCCGGCGUCCGGGAACGCUCAGGAGCCGGAGGAGCCGGAAAGCGCCGGGACCCCUCGCGGGGCCUCUGAGCGGCGCGGGCGGACCCGAGCCCCCAGCCCGCUGGCGCCGCUGCCCGCCAGGCCCCGGGGGCGGCGGCCAAGAUGUCCGUGCCUAUGAAAAAAUGAGGGCUUCCAGACUGUGCUGAUGUGAGCCCCGCCAUCCGUUCUGGUUCAGAGCAUAAUCGUCUCGUCUUCAGAAAGAAGGAAGACAGAACAUGCCUGCCAAGCCCUUCCUCUCUUCUGUUCUGCUCUCCUGGAAAGUUCUGGACUUCUCUGGCCCAGGGCCUCAGGGGACUGGCCAGCCCUGCUCCUGUGGGCACUGGGCAGAGGGACAAGGCGGACCACCUGAGCCUGCUGGAGGGCCGAACGUGCUGGCCAAAGCGCUCUAUGACAAUGUGGCCGAGUCCCCGGAUGAGCUCUCCUUCCGCAAGGGUGACAUCAUGACGGUGCUGGAGCAGGACACGCAGGGCCUGGACGGCUGGUGGCUCUGCUCGCUGCAUGGGCGCCAGGGCAUCGUGCCUGGGAACCGCCUCAAGAUCUUGGUGGGCAUGUAUGAUAAGAAGCCAGCAGGGCCUGGCCCCGGCCCUCCCGCCACCCCGGCCCAGCCUCAGCCUGGCCUCCAUGCCCCAGCGCCUCCGGCCUCCCAGUACACGCCCAUGCUCCCCAACACCUACCAGCCCCAGCCAGACAGCGUCUACCUGGUGCCCACUCCCAGCAAGGCUCAGCAAGGCCUCUACCAAGUCCCGGGUCCCAGCCCUCAGUUCCAGUCUCCCCCAGCCAAGCAGACAUCCACCUUCUCGAAGCAGACACCCCAUCACCCGUUUCCCAGCCCGGCCACAGACCUGUACCAGGUGCCCCCAGGGCCUGGAGGCCCUGCCCAGGAUAUUUACCAGGUGCCACCUUCUGCCGGGAUGGGGCAUGACAUCUACCAGGUCCCCCCGUCCAUGGACACACGCAGCUGGGAGGGCACGAAGCCCCCGGCAAAGGUGGUGGUGCCCACCCGCGUGGGGCAGGGCUAUGUAUACGAGGCCGCCCAGCCGGAGCAGGACGAGUACGACAUCCCGCGACACCUGCUGGCCCCGGGGCCACAGGACAUCUAUGAUGUGCCCCCGGUUCGGGGGCUGCUUCCCAGCCAGUAUGGCCAGGAGGUGUAUGACACACCCCCCAUGGCUGUCAAGGGUCCCAAUGGCCGAGACCCGUUGCUGGAGGUGUAUGACGUGCCCCCCAGUGUGGAGAAGGGCCUGCCACCGUCCAACCACCACGCAGUCUACGACGUUCCUCCAUCGGUGAGCAAGGAUGUGCCCGAUGGCCCACUGCUGCGUGAGGAGACCUACGAUGUGCCCCCCGCCUUCGCCAAGGCCAAGCCCUUUGACCCGGCCCGCACCCCACUGGUACUGGCUGCGCCCCCUCCAGACUCCCCGCCGGCCGAGGACGUGUAUGACGUGCCGCCCCCGGCUCCUGACCUCUACGACGUGCCCCCUGGCUUGCGGCGGCCUGGCCCGGGCACCCUGUACGAUGUGCCCCGUGAACGGGUGCUUCCUCCUGAGGUGGCUGAUGGUGGCGUGGUCGACAGUGGUGUGUAUGCGGUGCCUCCCCCAGCUGAACGUGAAGCCCCGGCAGAGGGCAAGCGCCUGUCGGCCUCCAGCACCGGCAGCACACGCAGCAGCCAGUCUGCGUCCUCCUUGGAGGUGGCAGGGCCGGGCCGGGAACCCCUGGAGCUGGAAGUUGCUGUGGAGGCCCUGGCACGGCUGCAGCAGGGUGUGAGCGCCACCGUUGCCCACCUUCUGGACCUGGCAGGCAGCGCCGGUGCGACUGGGAGCUGGCGUAGCCCCUCUGAGCCACAGGAGCCGCUGGUGCAGGACCUGCAGGCUGCUGUGGCCGCUGUCCAGAGUGCCGUCCACGAGCUGUUGGAGUUUGCCCGCAGCGCGGUGGGCAAUGCUGCCCACACAUCUGACCGUGCCCUGCAUGCCAAGCUUAGCCGGCAGCUGCAGAAGAUGGAGGACGUGCACCAGACGCUGGUGGCACAUGGUCAGGCCCUCGACGCUGGCCGGGGAGGCUCUGGAGCCACCCUUGAGGACCUGGACCGGCUGGUGGCCUGCUCGCGGGCUGUGCCCGAGGACGCCAAGCAGCUGGCCUCCUUCCUGCACGGCAAUGCCUCACUGCUCUUCAGACGGACCAAGGCCACUGCCCCGGGGCCUGAGGGGGGUGGCACCCUGCACCCCAACCCCACUGACAAGACCAGCAGCAUCCAGUCACGACCCCUGCCCUCACCCCCUAAGUUCACCUCCCAGGACUCGCCAGAUGGGCAGUACGAGAACAGCGAGGGGGGCUGGAUGGAGGACUAUGACUACGUCCACCUACAGGGGAAGGAGGAGUUUGAGAAGACCCAGAAGGAGCUGCUGGAAAAGGGCAGCAUCACGCGGCAGGGCAAGAGCCAGCUGGAGUUGCAGCAGCUGAAGCAGUUUGAACGACUGGAACAGGAGGUGUCACGGCCCAUAGACCACGACCUGGCCAACUGGACGCCAGCCCAACCCCUGGCCCCGGGGCGAACAGGCGGCCUGGGGCCCUCGGACCGGCAGCUGCUGCUCUUCUACCUGGAGCAGUGUGAGGCCAACCUGACCACACUGACCAACGCCGUGGACGCCUUCUUUACCGCCGUGGCCACCAACCAGCCGCCCAAGAUCUUUGUGGCGCACAGCAAGUUCGUCAUCCUCAGCGCCCACAAGCUGGUGUUCAUCGGGGACACACUGUCACGGCAGGCCAAGGCUGCUGACGUGCGCAGCCAGGUGACCCACUACAGCAACCUGCUGUGCGACCUCCUGCGCGGCAUCGUGGCCACCACCAAGGCCGCUGCCUUGCAGUACCCAUCGCCUUCCGCGGCCCAGGACAUGGUGGAGAGGGUCAAGGAGCUGGGCCACAGCACCCAGCAGUUCCGCCGCGUCCUAGGCCAGCUGGCAGCCGCCUGAGGGUGGUGACCCCAGGAGGGAGGCAGGGGAGGGGUGCGGCGGUCCCAGCUCCCUGGCUCCCAUGUCAAGAGUCGCUGUGCCACAGGCUUAGGGACAGGACCCCAGCUCUGCGUCGGUCCUGGUGCCCUGGAUGCCCAGGAAUCUGUAUAUAUUUAUGGCCGGGCAGGGUGUGGGGCCAUGCCUCCUCAGGAGCCGAAGCCCAGGGGCCGGCCAGUGGCCUUCCCCAGCAUGCACCACGGGCCCGGGUUGGGUCACCAGACGGGGCUGGAGUGUGAGGGUCCUGCAGCCUGCAGGACCUCGUGCCACCCCGAGGGCUGAGCCUGGUCCCACGAGGGUGCCGUGUCCCCUGACAGGGCCAGUGCAGUUUGGUGUGUCCUCCGCCUUACCAGGAGAAGAACCUGAAGAACUAUUUUUCGUUAUUGGUUUUCCAAUCAUUUGACUAAGAGUCUCCAUUUAAAUAAAGUUUUUAAAAGGAAGAGCAGCUGCCUGAGGGUGGCAGAUGAGAGCAGCCCGGGGUGGGUGACGGUUCUGGGGAAGGCACCCGGGGGCAAGGGCCAUGCGUGGCAUCUCCCGGGAGGGCAGAGGAGGAGUGGGUCUCUCUAGAAGAAAACCAAGGAACGCCGAGGCUGGGUGUCUCCUGGAGGCGGGGUGAGGCCUGCAGCUGGCCACAAGGCCCUGGGAGCCAGGGCAGAGCCUGGGCCCAAGAAAGGGGGCAGUUUCAGAGCUGCAGGGUCUGGGGCCCAGAAAGCACAGCCUGGGCAUGGCCCCUGCAACCCUAGGGAGCUGCCACAGUGAGCACCUGCCCAUGCCCACAGCUGGCAUCUGGAGUGAGGGCAGAUUGGGGCAGGAACAGCUGCACAAGGGGACGGGUUCCUGUGAGCCGAGGGCACCGCUGGGGGCUGCAUCCAGAGCUCUGCUUAAAAGAAUCUCAUCCCAGCCUGCGGAACUCCCGAAGUGCACAUGGAAUUAUACCUGGACCUGGCAUCUGAGUUGGGAGGGAGGGGCUUGGAGAAGACCCUUGCCCUGGGCAAGUGUGUCCCCCUUCGUGGCUCCCCCACCCAGCAGCCCGCAGCCCAGAUGGAAGCUUCAGGGUGCUUGGAACCCCUGGUGCUGCUCCCAGCCCUGACCGUUCUGCAUAUGAACAUGGGCCUUGGUUUCCCCAUCUGUAUGAAGAAGGGAGUAGGGCUGGGUGAUUCGCAAGCCCUCCUGAUCUUACCUCUACAGAGGUUGUCCCCGUGACAGCAUCUGUCCCCCCACCUCAGCCACAUCAUGCUCAGCCCACCUGCCUUGGUGAGGACACAGAGGUAAAGGUGUAUGCAGUUGCUCUCAA